GCACUCGCUGCCCACAAAGCGCCAGCUGAGGGGCCGCUGCGGGUGGAGUGCGGCGGAGUCGGCCUCGCGACCCCAGCUUGAUCCGCCGCCUGCUGCACCGCGCCUCCGCCGCGUUCCUGCGCGUCCCGAGCCCCGACGGCCGCGUGAGUCCCGUCCGUGCGGGGAAGGCAGGGCCGGGUCGGCGCCGCCUGUGGAGAGGACCCGGCGGCCGGGCCUGCUUGGAGCCGGGCGCGGUGGCAGCGGCGGCAGCGGCGGCGACUUCCGAGGCCCGGGCUAGACAGCGCAGGGCCAUGGCUGAGGCGGCCCCGGCCCCGGUAAGGGCGGCCGCGCGCGAGUGUUGUGAGCCCCCGAGACCCAGACCCCGAGGGAGGAAGGCGGGCGGGCAGGGAGCUGCCAGGCAUAGGCGCCGUUCUCGGGUCCCGCCGGCCACGUCGCCUGUCGCCCGUGCUUGGCGGCUGCAGCCUCGCGUGAGGGGACUUAGCGGGUGGGUGUGAAACCGCCCACCCGGGGACACCAGGCUGGGCCGCAGGUCUGAGGGGCACUCGCAGGCAGCUAUGAGACCCGGGGCCCUGCAGUUGGGUUGAAGUCGAGGGGGUGCCUGCUGCGUGUCAGCCCCACGCCUGCCCGCCAGACGCGCAGCGGGGUUGGGCUGGGGAGCCGUCAGCCAUUCUCGCGGCCGCGGGAGCGUUCGUCACCAGCAAUCUGAGCGGUGGCGCGGGCGGCAUUUAAGUGUGCGGAGGCGCAUUCCCGCCGCGCUGCGUGACGCCUGGGCUCCCGGCACCGGACUCGGGACACGCGGGAGGCCCUCCCGAAAUAGCUGCCGAAUGAAUGACAUCUGAAUGGGACUCCGAGUGCCUUACAUCCCUGCAGCCCCUUCCUCUUCCUACACCCCCAGCAGCAAAUGAGGCACACCUGCAGACAGCAGCUAUCUCUCUGUGGACAGUGGUGGCCGCCGUGCAGGCUAUAGAGAGGAAGGUGGAGAUCCACAGCCGGCGACUCCUACACCUGGAAGGUCGGACAGGGACAGCAGAGAAGAAACUAGCCAGCUGUGAAAAGACAGUUACCGAGCUUGGGAACCAGCUGGAGGGCAAGUGGGCCGUGCUGGGAACCCUGCUGCAGGAGUACGGGCUGCUGCAGAGGCGGCUGGAGAACUUGGAGAACCUGCUGCGCAACAGGAACUUCUGGAUCCUGCGGCUCCCUCCAGGUAUUAAGGGAGAUAUCCCAAAGGUGCCUGUGGCAUUUGAUGAUGUCUCCAUCUACUUUUCCACUCCAGAGUGGGAAAAAUUAGAAGAAUGGCAAAAGGAACUUUACAAGAAUAUCAUGAAGGGCAACUACGAGUCUCUCAUCUCCAUGGAUUAUGCUAUAAAUCAACCUGAUGUCUUAUCUCAGAUUCAACCAGAAGGGGAACAUAAUACAGAGGACCAGGCAGGGCCAGAGGAAAGUGAGAUUCCCACAGACCCCAGUGAAGAGCCUGGUAUUUCAACAUCAGAUAUUCUGUCUUGGAUUAAACAAGAAGAAGAGCCUCAGGUUGGGGCCCCACCGGAGUCCAAGGAGAGUGACGUGUACAAAAGCACUUAUGCUGAUGAAGAGCUUGUCAUCAAAGCUGAAGGCCUUGCUAGAUCCUCGUUGUGCCCUGAGGUUCCAGUCCCUUUCUCUUCUCCACCAGCAGCAGCAAAGGAUGCUUUUUCAGAUGUGGCUUUCAAAAGCCAGCAGUCUACAUCCAUGACACCUUUUGGACGUCCAGCCACUGACCUGCCUGAAGCCUCUGAGGGACAAGUGACUUUUACUCAGUUGGGUAGCUAUCCCCUCCCACCUCCAGUUGGCGAGCAGGUGUUCUCAUGCCACCACUGUGGCAAGAAUCUCAGCCAAGACAUGUUGCUGACCCACCAAUGUAGCCAUGCUACUGAGCACCCCUUACCCUGUGCCCAGUGCCCUAAGCACUUUACUCCACAGGCGGACCUCAGCAGCACCUCCCAGGACCAUGCCAGCGAGACACCCCCCACCUGCCCACACUGUGCCAGGACUUUUACUCACCCAUCAAGACUUACCUACCAUCUUCGGGUCCAUAACAGCACUGAGCGUCCUUUCCCCUGUCCUGAUUGCCCCAAGCGCUUUGCUGACCAGGCUCGACUCACCAGCCACCGGAGAGCUCAUGCAAGCGAAAGGCCCUUCCGCUGUGCCCAGUGCGGCAGGAGCUUCAGCUUGAAAAUCAGCCUCCUGCUCCACCAGCGGGGUCAUGCACAAGAGCGCCCUUUCUCCUGCCCUCAGUGUGGCAUUGACUUCAACGGCCACUCGGCCCUGAUCCGCCACCAGAUGAUCCACACAGGCGAGCGUCCUUACCCCUGCACUGACUGCAGUAAGAGCUUCAUGCGCAAGGAGCACCUGCUGAACCACCGGCGGCUGCACACAGGCGAGCGGCCCUUCAGUUGUCCUCACUGUGGCAAGAGCUUCAUCCGCAAGCACCACCUAAUGAAACACCAGCGCAUCCACACCGGGGAGCGGCCCUACCCCUGCUCCUACUGUGGCAGGAGCUUCCGCUACAAACAGACACUCAAGGACCACCUCCGUUCAGGCCACAAUGGAGGCUGUGGGGGUGAUAGUGACCCAUCAGGUCAGCCACCCAACCCACCAGGUCCCCUCAUAACUGGGCUUGAAACUUCUGGCCUGGGUGUCAACACUGAAGGUCUAGAGACCAACCAGUGGUAUGGGGAAGGGAGUGGAGGGGGAGUUUUGUAAAUCCAAAUCUCUGUGGCUUCAUGCUUGUAUAUGCUCACAGCAGGGCACAAAAUCCAAGAGAAGGUCUGUGAGCCCCAUCCAACACCCACAGUAAUUAUUAUCUGGCACAUCAAUGAAUUUGGGGUCCUAUACACUUGACUAGAGACAUGCUUGUGUUUUGGAAUUUCACACCCUUACAAGAAUACCACAUUUUGAAACCCAGAAAGACCUGGAAAGGAGCCCAGCAUGUCCAUCUUUUCAAAGAUACAACAAAAGCAGAAGUUACAAGAAUAUUGCGGAGAGGUUGGAAAGCAGGAUUUAACCUCUAGUUCUCUUGUUCUCAGAGAACAGCAGGUUGAUAGUAGAUUAUGUCUCUAGGUAGAGACAGAUACAUGAGAAGAGCCUCCAAAACUGGAAGCCCAUCAUAAGGCAUGAGAAUGUUUAACUAUAAAGCCUUUUAUUAGUUCUUUGAUAGCUAAGAUGGUUGUUGGAGAAAGUGCUUAAGCCACUGUUUAUGUUGCUGCCUCCUCUCUCAAAACCAGCCAAGAUCUGUUCACACACCUCUGUGGCUGUCUUUCCCUGAAACAUGGUAACUCAAGACUGCCUGCCUAGGUUUCUUAGAUUAAUUAUUCACAUAAAUUUUGUUUAAUAUUGGUUGAACAAGAAAUCUGACUUUAAAAGAUUAUUAAGGAGAAUAUUCCUUAACUAUACUGGCUUGAUUUGAAACAGGCUCUUAUUGCCAUUUAAACUGCCAGAAAUCUUUGCCAAGGUCCUGGUUAAAAAAAUUGGAAACGGUUUUCUUAGCCCCAGCUUUAAAAGCUAGAGAUCUCAGAGAAAUAGCUGGCUUAACAAUGACAGAACAGCUUAAAAUUUGUGCCUACACCAUGUUCUGAGAGUCGUUCACAUCAAAUUCUUAUCUUUUCCAAGCCAGUAAGUUGGCUUCUCCAUUCCUGGUGUCUGAUAUUCUUGACAAUCAUCAGCAACAAAGAUCACAGCACUUUCCAGAAGCAUGGAGCUUCAGAAAGUGCCAGUGAACUCUUGGUCCUCAGUAGUGAGAUGAUAACAGUGUUAUAAUGCAGCUUCCUUGAGCCAUCAGAGAGAGUGUAUGUUCACCCUAUCUGGCUGUAUCCCAUUGGCAGUGGACAGAUUGAGGAAAUUCCUAGAUCACUGAGAGCUAAGCACCAUGCAUAGACAACAGUUUGUUCUUGCCUGUGUUGCUUUUAGGGACUUUGACUACCACAUGUUCUUUUCUUGGGGUGAUUUAAUCACCUGGGAGCAUCUGAGUCUGCUCCUAAGUGGCUUUGCAACUGGGCCUAAGUUCUGUUUCCUUUAUGGAUCUCAAAUUUUCAUCUGCACAAUGAGGCUGUUGAAAGGAAAAAAAGUGAGCCUCUAGGAAUUAUUCAAAAAAAGUCUGUGAUACAUUCCUUUUCCUGCCAAAGUUCUGUCUCUGUCUUUGGCUUCUGUCCAGGCAAAGCUAAAUAAGACAGCAAAGUCAAAGCAGAUAAAUUCUUGUUGAAACUUGACUAAAAUUUAUUUGAUUUGUUGUUUUACUCCCACUUGGAAUCCUGAGGUAGAAGACAGAAUGCAGAAGUCUUACAUCUUGGGCAGGAAACUGGUUUAUUCCUAUACUCUUGUUUCCUCUGCUUCUUCCUGAGGUCUAGAACAAGGUCUGGAAAUGUUUAGACAGGAUAUUUUCUUGAUGAAGUGAUAAGGAAAGGACCCAUUUUUUUGCUCAUCACCUAGCCCAUCCUUCACUCUCUCUAGUUAUGCAUAACAACACUAGAAGAAGGUGUUAGCCCAGCUAACUUUGCUUCUGGGAAGGCUAUGUCUGAACAUGUUGCUCUGUAGGAUAAUCACACUUAGAAAACAUCUGCUCCAUGACAUUCACAAUACCAGGGACCAUGGGAGACACAAGAAAUGUGUGUCUGCUGUCAUAACUUACAGUGAAAAAGCCCAAUAAUACAGAACAAGACAUGAUGGGCAAUACCCUAGCAUAUUGGGAUUAAGAGCUUUCUAGCCAGAAUCUGGACCUAUACCAUGGGAAAAUUUAGGGGUGCUGGGAAUCCCAAAGCCAAGGUUCUGGCUUCAUUGGCAACCCACUAGGAACUUGAAUGUGAGAUUCAGCUCUAGUUUGCACCUUGAUUUCCCCAGUGAAAAGGGAGAAGAGCCAAAGUAUUGUCUAGGUGCUGAGUUCCCUUUUCUGAGUGGAUUUCAAGCAUUUGCCAGGGUAUGCUGGAGGAGGGACUCCUAAAGUAGGUGAGAUGUGGGACUAGGUAACACUUUAAAUACUUUUUUACUCAAAGAUUUGCCAAGAACACAGCUUAUUAGUGAAAGAGACCUGUGGAUUGAAAUGGCUGCAGAUAGAUCCCGCAGUCCCUUCUGAAAGGAACUGUGUAGCCAGCAGGGACCUAAACUUUGGCAAAAAGUGAACACAAUUCAAAUACGAAUGAAGGAAGAGCCCUCAGAUGGAACGAAAGGCGAUGUGCAAGGCCAUCCCAGAGAGACGGAAGCAGGUGCGAUACUAAGCCUCAGCCCAAGAAUAAAAGAGAGUUCAACUGUUACUCUUUUCUUUCAUCAAUCCCCUAUCAGUUAGAACUGCAGGCCAGUUCCAAAGAGUGUUUGCUUAAGAUUCAAAAGUGGGUAAGUAAAAUGGAUCAGUGGGAAGGAUAAGGUGUCCAACAGAAAGUGUGGAGGAGAAACUCUUGGCCUAUCAAGUGCUCCUGAGAGAAACCAUGCAAUUUAACACUUCAGUUAAAGAAAUACAUGAGAACUGCUUGUCAUGACCAGACAAGAUAGGAAAGGGGAAACCCCAGAAACGUGCUCUUCAUCUGUCAGCCUUUUGGACCAAGAAGCUGUCACUAUCACACAUAAGCACCAUUCCCUUAGAGUGGAUCCAGGUGUUGACUAUAACCAGAUUUACUCUUUGCUUACUAGGUUUUCCAUUGUCACCAUUGGAUGAACCUCUGGUUUAGCCACAGUUGUGAAAAUAAAUGGAAGUUGGUUGAUUGUCUAGAAAGUGCAAGAAGAUGGCCCUGCUCCUUUUCUGCUGAACAUUUAGUAUUGGAAACUCCUACUUCCCUUUUCAUUAAUAAUGUGUGCAAGUUUCCUAUUAGCGGGGAAGGUGUGGGGCUCUGCUGGGCUUCUCUUGAGCAUAUCUGAGAAGUGAUGUUCAUGUCUAUCUCAACCAGGACCAGACCCUGUGACUUACUCGGUAAUAACAGUCCACACAAGCCUCGUUGAUAUUAAAAAAAAAAAAAAAAAA